AAAAUAGCUUUCAUUUUAAGAAUGUUGUGUGACUCAUUAGAAAGGAGUUUGUCAGCUCAUCAGAUCUUAAGUUUUACCUUUUGAAGUAGACAGGUUUCGUCAUGUGUAAAGAAAUGAUUUCAGUCUUACAUAUUUACUUAGAAGCCAUGGAAACGUUGGUUAAUUUAUUAGUCAUCAAAUAAUUUGCCAAAUUUUUAAAUGGCUAACUUGUACAUAUAUAUCACUUAAAGCAAGCUUGUCCAAAUUGCAGGUGGCCCAGGACAGCUUUGAAUGUGGCCCAACACAAAUUUGUAAAUUUUCUUAAAAUAUUAUGUGAUUUUUUUUUAAGUUCGUUAGCCAUCGUUAGUGUUAGUGGAUUUUAUGUGUGGCUCAAGACAAUUCUUCUUCUUUCAACAUGGUCCAGGGAAGCCAAAAGAUUGGACACCCCUGAAAGUAUACACAAUGCCUGAAUGUUACAUUUGCAACUGGGUUAUAUUUAAUUUUUUUUUUUAGUCUCUCCUUUCACUUUUGCCAACCCUUUGGUAAAUUUAAUCCAUUGAGUUAAGUAAGAUGUUCUUUGUAUCAUGUAGAAUGAAAGAAACUAUGGGGGAGAAAAAGAAAACAAAAGUGUCUUUCAAGUAUUCAGAUUAUAGUAGACAUUCCAGAUUCAGUCAAAGGAUGGUUAAAAAAACUAUGCAUUCAUUCAUUUAUUCAUUUGUAUUUAUUGAUUAAUUUGUCCACACAGUAAGUAUUUACUGUCAGGAUUACAAAAGUGAGAGCACCUUUUCCUUGUUCACAAGGAGUGUGUUAACAACCCAGUCCUGUAAAAGAAUUCAGGGUUUCAACCCAUGUGGCAAUUGUCCUUAAAGAAUCUGAGUGUCUUCACCAAGCUCUCCUUUCUUCUUGACUCUCCAUCUAGCUUUCAAAGAAAUUCAUACUUGUGCAUAGUGGAUUUUUUUUCUUUGUAUAAUCAUUUGGGGAGUUACAAAAGGAAAUAAUGAAGGACUAAAUAAAGAAAUUAAGUUUUUUAUAAGAUGUAGACUGGGUACACGGUUCAUGCCUACAAUCCCAGCACUUUGGGAGGCUGAGGUGGGAGGAGCACUUGAACCCAAAAGUUUGAAACCAGCCUGGGUGACAUAAUAAUACAUUGUCUGUACAAAAAAUAUUUAUUUAAAAAAAUUAGCUAGGUAUGGUGGCAUGCACCUGUAAUCCCAGCUACUUGGGAGGCUGAGGGGGAGGAUCACUUGAAUCUGAUAUGUCAAAACUACAGUGAGCCGUAAUCACACCACCGCAUUCCAGGGCAGGUUUCACAGGGAAACCGUCUCAAAAAAAUAAAUAAAUAAAUAAAGAUGUUUAUAAGGUGUAAAUUCAAAUGCAUUUCACAACCAAAUAUUUCAUAUGCUUUGCGUGUUUUCCAAUUAAAUGUAGAAGGUUGGCCUAGGAGAGUAUUUUUUAAAUAGAAUCCUGAAAAAAAAAUAUAACCCUUGGCCAUGUGUUAUGAAGUUACAAUAUUCACUAGAAUUUAUUUGUGUCUUGCUGAUAAUAAUCAACAAUUUAUUGAUAAUGCUUAUAAGUAUACAAUCAUUUGUUACCACUGGAAAAGGAUCCAGUGGGAACGUUCUUUAGGGCUCCAAUUAGAUUAGUUUUUUAACUUUUUCUUUUCUAACUUUUAAGUUCAGGGGUACAAAUGCAGGUUUGUUACAUAGGUAAACAAACUUGUGUCUUGAGGGUUUUUUGUACAAAUUAUCUCAUCACCCAGAUAUUAAGCCUAGUACCCAUUAGUUAUUUUUUGUGAUCCUCUUCCUCCUCCCACCCUUUACCCUGUGAUAGGCCCCAGUACUGUGUUGUUCCCCUCUAUGUGUCCAUGUGUUCUCAUCAUUUAGCUCCUGCUUAUAUGUGAGAACAUUCGGUAUUUGGUUUUCUGUUCCUGCAUUAGUUUGCUAAGGAUAAUGGUCUCCAGCUCCAUCCAUGUCCAUCAAAGGACAAGAUCUCAUUCUUUUUUUAUGGCUGCAUAGUAUUCCAUGGUGUAUAUGUACCACAUUUUCUUUAUCCAGUCUAUCGUUGGUGGACAUUUAGGGUGAUUCCAUGUCUUUGCUCCAAUGACAGCUGGACCAGGGUCUUAUCAAAAGCAGCAUAUUUCCUUAAUCUGGAGAAGUUCUCCUUAAUCCAGAGAAGAUUUUUUUUUCAGAGAUAAGCAGGUUCAACGGCUCAGCCGCAGGUUAUUUUUGCCUAGCAAAGGCACUAACAAAAACAUGUGCACUGGCAAAAUACUGGAUUUCUACAUGGUAUAUUGAGGAAAAUGUUAUCUAGGACUUAAGGACAAAAACCCAAAUAUUAUUUGGCACAUCACCAAUUCACAAAUACCAAUUACCUGACAAUUUAUUGCUAUAAUAAUCUGCAAAAUAAUGAAGUCACUAAAUUAGCUCUUUGCAAAAAAAGUUUUAAUUAGCCACCUGUAAAGUGUUUAGCAAUUCUUAUGUUGCUGAAGCACAAUUAAUUUUUUAUGAAUGGUCAUUUCUGGUGUUUUUGAAAGAUACUUCAUUUAAAUUUUUUCUCCAUAGUUUCUUUCAUUCUACAUGUAAAAAGAACAUCUUACUUAAACACAAAUGGAUUAAAUUUACCAAAGGGUUGGCAAAAGUGAAAGGAGAGACUAGAAAAGAAAUGAUAUAUAACGCAGUGGCAAACAUAACAUUCAGGCAUUGUGAAUGUUUUAAAUGAUACGUAUGUACAAACUCGCCCAGAAAAAUCUAAUUUCUACAAAUUGUGUGAGUUGUUAUUCAAAACCAGUUUUUGGUAAAUCAGUAACUGUGCAUCAAUCAGUAGAUUAACUGCCAAAUCACCAAUUAUCGGUUCCUAUUUAUGACCCAUUGUAAAAUAAAGAUUGCAAUUAGAACCCAUUUGUAGCACAUCCAUUAGUUCCUUCUCAGGAACCCAAACAAUCACAAUGUCAUUAAAAUUGUUUUUUGUCUUUCUACUUCUUCUGUUAUUAUAUAAACUGCUCCAGAGUGCAAAGGUUGAUUUCAGAUGUUGAAAGCAAAAUAGUUGAUAUUUCUACUGAGAAACUGGGAUUACAUCAUCUUUUUUUCUAGGACUACUCUAAUUCCCAUAUUUGGAGUUCUUCCAUUACUGAUUAUUUCUACACUUCAGGAAUUCUCUUAGUAAUUUUUAUAUGUGCAGCUUCAAGACAAUCCUUAUUAGAUGGUCAUUUUACUUCCACUUUUGGUACGACAUUCUUUCUUCCCAUGAUGUGUCAAUGGCUCUAUGUAUCCUAUCAUUGGUGACACAAUCCCUUCUAUAACACUGGAUACUUACAAUCAGUAAUUAACUUAAUGUGUAGCUCAAUCACUAAUGUUAAAAGUUUAUCUUUUAAAAAUGACUAAAUUCAUAAAAUAAUGUCUAGGUGUUUUUUGACAAUCUGGUCCUAAGUGAUCUUUUUCUUUUUCACAGGGAAAUGGGGGAAAAUCAGACAAUGGUCACAGAGUUCCUCCUACUGGGAUUUCUCCUGGGCCCAAGGAUUCAGAUGCUCCUCUUUGGGCUCUUCUCCCUGUUCUAUAUCUUCACCCUGCUGGGGAACGGGGCCAUCCUGGGGCUCAUCUCACUGGACUCCAGACUCCACACCCCCAUGUACUUCUUCCUCUCACACCUGGCUGUCGUCGACAUCGCCUACGCCUGCAACACGGUGCCCCAGAUGCUGGCGAACCUCCUGCAUCCAGCCAAGCCCAUCUCCUUUGCUGGCUGCAUGACGCAGACCUUUCUCUGUUUGAGUUUUGGACACAGCGAAUGUCUCCUGCUGGUGCUGAUGUCCUACGAUCGUUACGUGGCCAUCUGCCACCCUCUCCGAUACUCCGUCAUCAUGACCUGGAGAGUCUGCAUCACCCUGGCCGUCACUUCUUGGACGUGUGGCUCCCUCCUGGCUCUGGUCCAUGUGGUUCUCAUCCUAAGACUGCCCUUCUGUGGGCCUCAUGAAAUCAACCACUUCUUCUGUGAAAUCCUGUCUGUCCUCAGGCUGGCCUGUGCUGACACCUGGCUCAACCAGGUGGUCAUCUUUGCAGCCUGCGUGUUCUUCCUGGUGGGGCCACCCAGCCUGGUGCUUGUCUCCUACUCGCACAUCCUGGCGGCCAUCCUGAGGAUCCAGUCUGGGGAGGGCCGCAGAAAGGCCUUCUCCACCUGCUCCUCCCACCUCUGCGUGGUGGGACUCUUCUUUGGCAGUGCCAUCAUCAUGUACAUGGCCCCCAAGUCCCGCCAUCCUGAGGAGCAGCAAAAGGUCUUUUUUCUAUUUUACAGUUUUUUCAACCCAACACUUAACCCCCUGAUUUACAGCCUGAGGAACGGAGAGGUCAAGGGUGCCCUGAGGAGAGCACUGGGCAAGGAAAGUCAUUCCUAACUGGUGUGACAUUUGACUCUCCCUCCUCAGUCAUCUCCUGGAAUCUUGGUACCAAAUACCACCUAAGUUCACUACUCUCUUUAUAUCUGAGACUAAAUGAACCAAGAGACUCUGUAAAGCAUUCCUUUUUCCUGCCUGGGAAGUAUUUAGUUUUUGAUGCAUUUGUUAUACUUAACAUUUUUUAAUUUAAGCACUUAUUGAGUUGAGAAUGUCGGGGAAAGAUUUAUUUUGUACACUGCUAUGAGUCCAGAAGUUUAAAACAGACACUCCACCUGUGACUUAGUCAGGUAUGCUCAGUAGUAGAGGAAUAGCAGUUAUUACCAGAUAAAGUCAUAUCUAUAAAAAGUUUUUAAAAAUACAGCCACAGGCAGAGACUCCAGAACCCAUUGAUACCUCUGUCCAUUUUCAUCCUCAUUUGGAUGUUUCCCCUCAAUUGUACUUCCUUUCUUAUAAGCAGUAAAUGUACCUAAGUGCCUACUUCAGCUUGGAGGGAAAUUGAUUUUUAUAAAAUCCUACAAACUGACAAUUUCUGUUGUCAGAGAGAGUGAAUCCAUAAACAUUCAGCUGGCAAUCUGAAGCAAUUACACAACAAAAUCCACUUUCCAACCUGCCCUGAGAUUGUGAUGGUCACUUGUUUCUACUCUUCUCACCUCCUCCAGGGGACUGUCUAUGAUUGUCUCUAAAUAAGCACAUGCUCUUCACUUAGAGGAAGUUAGUACCACCACACAACUUUUCACUGCUGGGGACGAAUGGAAAGCCCCACACAGAGACAAUUCAAUGGAAAAAAGCGUUUUAAUAAUGUUAAUAGUUAGCAUUAUUAUAAAUUACUCUGCACCAUCCACUGCACAUUGAUAGGUACUUUAUAGAGAUAACCUCAGUUUAUCAUUAUAGCCAAUUCAUUUCCCAUUAUUAUCCCAUUUUAUAGAUGUGAACUUUAAGCAGACGGUAAAUGUUAGACUCAUACCCAGACAAUCUGGCUCCCAAGCCUUCUUUACUUAACCAGGACAAUGUGGGACUUUAUUAGCAACAUUUCAAAUUAAGAAUAAGUCUAACCAAUCCUAACGUAGGAUAUGUUAAGUGAAUGUGGGUUUCUUCCCCAUCUAGAAUGUGCCAUGAUGAGGCCAGGAGAGUCAGAGAUUAUUUAUGGAAGGCUUCUUAUCCUGUUUGACGAGUCCUGUGGGCAUGGCUGCAAAGGAGGUUAAGAGAUUCAGAGGAACACAGAACACAGACAGGGUGGGAGUAGAGGCUGUUCUCAAUGAGAUUAGAGAGUAAGUUUAGAACUAUACUUGGUUCUGGGUAGUAAGAUCCAGAACAAAGACAUCUCUAGUUCACGUACAACACUCACAUGCUCACGUACAUGCGUGUGCACACACACACACACACACAUAUACGCACAGUGCUUAGUGAAGCACUAUUCCAAGAACCUUACAAGUAAGAGCUCUUUAAGUCCUCAUAAAAACCCUAUGAGGUAGAGACUAUUACUACUAUUUUUAGGCGAGAAAACAGAACUAUAGAGAGAUUAUAUAAUUUAACCAAUGCUCCCAGCUAAUAAGUACCUAGUCCAGAAUCAAAGAUAGGCAAUAUGACUGCUGAACCCAUAAUCGUAACCAUUAUAUAAAAAUCAAAGAGAUCAUGAAAUUUCCAAAGAUGAAGAGGAGGAGAGAUGAAAAGCAAUUUUCAAUCUCUAGCCAAAGAUAGGCAUUGGGCUCCAGACAGAAAAGUACUUAAAGCUGGGGGAAAAACAAACAAACAAACAAACAAACAAACAAACAAAAAACAGCUUUUUUUAUACUGGUGCGUGAAAUGAGAUGAGGUGGUAGCAAGAAGGAACUGUGACUCCAAGGGUCAGAGACGGAGGAGGAGCCUCUUGACGGGCAGGAUGGUGAAACCAAAAACAAUGGAUAAAACUUUUAAGUUGAUGGUUCAUCAAUUGAAGAACAUUAGAAAGUGUUUUUGUAAAUUAUCUAGCCGGGCAUGGCAACGUGUGCCUACAUCCCCAGCUAUUCGGGAGGCUGAGGCAAGAGGAUCACUUGAGCCAGGGAUUUUGAGGCUGCAGUGAGCCAUGAUCGCACCACUGCAUUCCAGCCUGGGUGACAGAGUGAGACCUUGUGUCCAACAAUAAUAACAAUGAAAUAAUUUAUUAAAUUUUUUAAAAUUACCCAAACUGGAUAUACAAUUUGUAAUUCCAUUGCUGCCGAACAGUUUUUAAACGGUUGUUUAGUUUCACGGCAGAUGCUGCAUACUGCAUUGCAACUAACACUGGGAAGGGAUACAUUCAAGUGGCAGGACAAAGGUGAGGAGCUCUAAUACCAGGGGUAGGUUUCAAGGGAUGAAUACUCCCCUGGUACCAGAGGAGCAGCAGGAAAUCAUGGUGUGCAGAAACCAUGUUCAGGCGGUUGCCUGUGUGGACCCUAAAUUCUGUGUGUGCAGUCCUCUCUUAGGAUUGGCCCAGGCAUCCAAGAAGCCCACGAUGCUGCCUACCCCUUAAAUACACAAGGUGCGUACCGGAGGCCCUGGUUCUAGUUCCAGAUGUACCAUUUGCUAGCUGUGUUUUUUGCAGAGAAGUCCCUUAAACUGCUUAAGCUUCAGUCCUUCAUCUGAAAAUUAUGCAUAUGGAAGCUGUUUAGGACACCACAGAGUGCCACUGAAAACCCAAAGCAAGAUGCAAAUGGACACAUUUUUUUUCUGAAGACUUAAAAGUGCUAUGUGAACAUAAGAUAAACUGUUAUGAUUACCCUGCUGUCAGAAGUUAUUUUAAUCCUGUCAGGGUUGCUAAACUUUCUGAUCUGGAACCAAAAUUGCUCUUUAAACAGGAAGAGCAUUGGUGCUGGUAGGUCACCUACGCCUUUGCCCUCAUGGCUUCCCCAUGUCCCCCCUAGAGGCACAGGAGGCCACUCACUCUUGGAGGGCAUAGCUGGACCAGGAGCAUGAGCUGUGGCCCAGACUCAGGGAACCUCUGUGAGUCAGCUGGCAAAGGCUCCCGGGGAGCCUGUCUCUGAAUCUGGUCCUAGCCCGUUCACUUGGAAAAAACAGGAGACUUCUCCCAAGGUCAAGGAAUUCAGAUUUUGGUUUUGGUUUCCAACUUUUUGUAAUCCUCAACCUGGGAUUUACAGUGCAUGUCUCAAUUAUGUUUCAUUCAUUGCUUCACAAAGGGAAGGACAAGCACUGGUUCAUCUCUUUACACCUAUACAUUCCUAGCACAGAGUGAGUACUCACAAAAAACAUACGGAAUACAUAGAGGACACUUUAUCUGUUGACCCCAUUUCCAAAUUUUCAGUGUUGAGCCAUCUUCUGAUUUCUAAACUUCUUUAAAUCCCUCUAAUUUUAGGUUAUACUACAGUAGAAAUUUAAUUGUAGCUGAUAAUUAUUGAGCACUUACUAUGUGGUUGGCACUGCAUAAAAUGCUUUAGAAAAAUUCUUACAUCAAAUAUGUGGAGUAGGUACUAAUACUAUCCUAACAUUAAAGGGGGGGAAAUAAAGUUUAGUGUAAUUAAUUAAUUUAUUCAAGGUCGCCAAAUCAUUCAGUGGUAGAAACAUGAAUCAAGACCAGGCAGUCUGACUGUAAAUAAAUUCUGAGCCACUCUCUUGCAGAGGACCUCCUGAUAUUCAUCUCCUGAAUGGUUGGCAACAGGCCUGUUCAUAGUAGACACACAAUAAACUUUGACUAAAUGAACAAAUGAGUGGUUGUGUUCAAAUUUCUACUCACAUCAUAUAGGCCUAGGGAUGUGUUACCCUUUAUUCUUUUUAUUUAUUUAUUUAUUUAUUUAUUUACUUAUUUAUUUAUUUGAGAAGGAGUCUUCUUCUGUUGCCCAGUCUGGAGUGCAGUUGUUGGCUCACUGCAACUUCUGUCUCCCAGGUUUAAGUGAUUCCCCUGCCUCAGCCUCCUGAGUAGCUGGGACUACAGGCGUGGGCCACCAUGCCUGGCUAAUUUUGUAUUUUUAGUAGAGAGGGGGUUUCCCCAUGUUGGCCAGGCUGGUCUCGAACUCCUGACCUCAGGUGAUCCACCCGCCUCGGCCUCCCAAAGUGCUGGGAACACAGGCGCGAGCCACCGUGCCUGGCCUAUUCUUUUAAGUUUGGAUAUCUUGUGCAUUUGGUUUGUCCAAUUCAUCCUUUUGGCAUAUUCUUAUGCAGUAGAUAUUAAUAAUCAAGAAUAUCCUAUUGCUCUAGGAUCACAGAGAAGAAAAGAAACAAUUUAGGGUUGAAAUUUAGCAUUUACUAUUAAAAAUGCUGGGAAUACUUAUUUAUGUUUUAUCGUAGGAGUCCAUGGCGAUUGCCUUCUCACAGAAGUGUGCCAAAUGACUGAAACUGUGAUUCCAGAAGGCCAGGAUGGUACUGGUGCUACACAGGAAGUCAUGUCAGGGUGUUGAUCUUGAAAACUCUGGCAAGAGGGUGGAGACAACUGUAGGCAAUAACUACUGGGAAUGAAAGGGAUGGGAAUUUGUGUGUUGUAGUCAGUUUCCUUGCCGCCUGAGAUUGGCACCCGCAGCAUCUUUGGCACGUGGACCAGGGAUUGCCAACUGCCGACCUGUAGGACUGGUGUUUACUGUUGGCUGUGAGUGUAGAGUACCAUUGUUAAAUACAGGUUCUUGAGAAUAGACAAAAAGGAAAGACAUUUGGAAUGCUGUCUCACUGGACUUCACAGCUCUCAUGUUUUCGCAGCCAGCAGAGAAGUGUCUUACAUCCCUUGCUUUCUUCAUAAAUUUUAAAUAGCAUUGGCUCAUUUUUAUCUGUGUUUUUCCAAGCUGUGUUUCUCUGUUUUUAAUUUUUGAAAUCAUGUUGUGCCAAAAGAAGAAGUGAAUCCUUGAACACGGUAUGAUUUGGUCAACAGAAUACUGGCUCAGCAUGAGAAUGUCUGGGCUCUCACGACAAUUCCCUCACUUACACACUGUGUGACCUCAGAAAAGUUGCUUAACUCCUCUGGACUUCCAUUUCCACACAUAUAAAAUAAAGAAUUGAACUAGAAAAACUUUAAGGUCACCUCUUGUUUUCUAAUUCCCUGUCUUUAUUAGUUUCUUCACAUUUCAUAUUAAUUUGGAUUUUCACUUUUGUCAAAGGAGUAUAAAAUAAAUUCCAUACAGAGAAAAUGAAAUGGACUUCUGAGGCUAACUGAAUCUCUCUGACCUUAAAUACAGUAGAACCCCAAAAAUACAUACUGGCCAGGCACGAUGGCUCAUGCCUGUAAUCCUAGCACUUUGGGAGGCCGAGGCAGGAGGAUCACUUGAGGCCAGGAGUUUGAGACCAGCCUGGCGAACAUGAUGAACCUUUUCUCUACUAAAAAUACAAAAACCAGCCAGGCAUGGUGGCAUGCGCCUGUAAUUCCAGCUACUUGGGAGGCUGGGGCACAAGAAUCGCUUGAUCCUGCAAGGCAGAGGUUGCAGUGAGCCAGGAUCAUGCCACUGCACUCCAGCCUGGGUGACAGAGGGAGACUCUGUUUCAAAAAAGGAAAAAAAAUAGUACAUACUGAAGUAAUUAAUUAGUUGACUAUUUUAGUGCUCUGGGAAAUAGAAAUUUCAUAAGACUGGCUAAAAGGUAACACGAAAUGCCCACCUUAAGGAAAGAAUAUUACUAGGAAUAACUUUGAUUGGGAAUGGUUCUAGGAACUAGACUAAAACAUAAAUAUCUAGUUUUGUACCCAUAUUACCCACAUUGUAGAUAUACUUUUAAGAGCUAGUAUUUGCUGAGAGCUUAUGAAAUGUCAGGCAUUGUGCUAAGGUACAUGCAUCAUUAUCAUGUCUCAACUUCAUAACAAUUCUAGUACCUUUAUUAUUAUUAUUACAAAAGAAGAGAUAGAGGUUCAGAGAUAGUAAGAAACUUUUCUAUGGUCACACAGCAAGUAUCUGACAUAACUUGGACUCUAAUCCAGGUGAGCCUGACUCCAUAACCACUGGGUCAUAUGGCCUCCCUCUAUCCUGGACUUACAGAAUCUUUUUCUGUGAACAGUUAAGUAAGGAUCAAGAAAAUCAGCCUUGAGAUCUAUUGUACAACUUGGUGAUGAUAGCUAAUAACAAUAGAUUGUAUUGUGAAAAAUGUUGACAGAGUAGAUUUUAAGUGUUCUCACCAUAAAAAUGACAAGGGUGUUAGAUAAUUCAUAUGGUAAUUUGCCCAAUUUAGUCAUUCCACAAUGUACAUACAUUUCAAAAUAUCAUUUUCUACAUGGUAAAUCUAUACAAUUUUGUCAAUUAAAAAAUAAAACACUUAUUUUACUUAAUUUUAUUUAUUUAUUUAUUUAUUUUUGAGAUGGAGUUUUGCUCUUGUCGCCCAGGCUGGAGUGCAAUGGCACAAUCUCAGCUCACUGCAACAUCCACCUCCCGAUUCAAGGGCUUCUCCUGCCUCAGGCUCCUGAGUAGCUGGAAUUACAGGCGGCCACCACCAUGCCUGCCUAAUUUUUUGCAUUUUUAAUAGAGACAGGGUUUCACCAUGUUGUCCAGGCUGGUGUUGAAUGCCUGACCUCAGGUGAUCCACCCGCCUCAGCCUCCCAAAGUGCUGGGAUUAUAGGCAUGAGCCACUGCAGCCGGCAGAAAAAAAUAAAACGUUUAAAAAGUCCACCAUCUUUACCACACACAAAGAAAAGAAAAUCAGCUUUAAGAAAAUGAUUAAAAUAUAGCUAACGUAGUCCCCAAUAUAUAUAACAAGCAAAAUAGUAAUACACAAACCAGUUUUUUAUUGGAAAAAAACACAUAGAUACAAGUAGAGACAGAUAAACUAUUUACAGUAGAACAAGUGACAGAGAAUAAUAAAUGUAAUGAAAGAUGUAUAGUUCCUCUAGUAAGUAAUAAAUUUUAAAGCACAAGAUACCAUUUUUCACCCAUUAGAUGGACAAAAAUUAAAAGAUGGAUACUUUCUAGCAUCGCUAAGCAUGUAGGCAAGUGGAUACUUCCCCACAGUCUUAAUAGAUUUCGGGGAAAUUUGGUCAUGUCUCUUCAAAAACUAAAUUGUUAGUUUUGUUUUGAUUUUUCAGAGACAGGGUUUCACUCUGUUGC